AAAGAAGACAGGCAUAUGUGAGAAGAAGCAAUCAGAAGAUUGGCAGGAUUUAGGAAUCUAUUUGAAAUAUUCAUUACCUAUUUUGAAUUGGUCUUAAAAAUUUAAAGAAAUAUAAAGCUGGAUAAUUAAAGAUAAAUAAUAAAGGAAGAAUACAAGGUUUCUAUGCUGUGAAGCAACUGAGAUUAUUAUGAUUUUGGGGCAGUGAAUUUGUUUCUAGAAGUUUUGUUGGAACUAAGGCAGAAAGGAAGAAGAACAAAUGACCUUGGAAUGAAAAACUUUAAGGAAAUAUUUACGCAUAGGGAUUGCAAUUAUUCAAAAAUCAUUUUAACUUGUCAUGUUAAUGAUAAGAGUGAUGAUCAGCAAAGUUACUCCACCUAACCACUAUGAAUGAUAGUCUUGUCUCACCAACCCCAGCCCAUCAUCUGUUGGACUUGGAGCUCACACUUUAAAAAAGAAGAUCAUUCUAACUGCCCCUCAUGACUACUGAAGAGGCUAUGCCUGAAAAAGCAAAAUGUCCUACAUUAGAGAUCACCAAGCAAGACUUUUUUCAAGAAGCAAAAACUCUCAUUGCCCAACAUUAUGAGAAAAUAAAUGAGAAUAAAGUUCAAGGUACUUCUAUAAAUGUUUUUAGAAAGAAACACCAAAAACCGAAAUCUGGCAAAUACAUACCUUUGGAGAUUGACAAAAAGGUAACACGUGAUGUGGUGCAAGAACAUCGGGCCGCACUCAGAAGGAUUUGCUUUCCCAAGGAGCUUUCCAAAAGCGAGCAUCUUCAGGAACCCCCACAACGAAUCUCCUUCAAGGAACCACACAUUUUUAGUAGAAGAGAAAGAUGCAGGCCCAUAGAUCUAAUUACAAAAGGACAAGUUAAAUUGGAUAAAAUCAUGACUAUUAUUGAACCAGUGAGUAAAAAAAUGGAGACAGCAAAGCAACAGCACUUUGAGGAGUCCAGAAACAGAAUGUUGGAAUUACUCUAUCCCUUUCCUGUCCAUCUUUACUUACAACCUGGGACCUCUAACUUGGAACUUCUGAAAGAACCUGACAAAGCAUUCUAUGACUGGAGAGGAUUUGUGCUGACAAGGUCUUUCCGUUUGGCUUGUGACUCCCGUCGAGUUAGUUUCUCUCAAUCAUCAUCAAUAUUUCGGGAUUAUUAUUCUAUUGUUUGCAGUUGGCAUAUAAACAUGCUACUGAUUUUCAAAACCUUUAAAACCCUUAUUAAAAAGGAGCGACAACCUAUCAAGCCAGAACCAAAAUCACAACCCAGGAUAAAAGGUACUCCAAAUAAAACUGAUAAACUUGACAGUAAAGUUAAAAGAAUUGGACCACACAUAGAAAUCUUCCAAGUGUUCCGAGAAAGAAAAAAAUUCAUGAUUACCCCAAAAUUGAUUAGAAUGGUCACCGUCAUGCAGGCACAUGUCAGGGGAUGGCUUGAACGGAAAAGAUUGCAAAGAGUAAUGACCAAGGCUUUGGAUCAUGGACCAGAUAUGAAAGCAGUUAUUAACAUGUAUGGCAGACUAAUCCACCGUGUUAGAUAUCGACGUGGUCUUUGGAGGACAAGACAAAUUCUCAACUUAGCAGAGCUAGAGGAGUGGAUGGACCGAAAAAAAUUCUAUGAAAUAAUGUUUGCUAAGAGGGAAGAUUGGCCAAAAAUUGAAAGAAAUGAGCUCCCCAAUUUCUUCAGUGACUGUGGUCAUUUCCCAACUCAGAAACAAGUUGAUGAUACUUGGGACCUGGUCCAUCAAGAUGGCAAAGAAAAAUAUUCUGAACUAAUCAAAAAGUCCAAAGCAAUUGAAAUGUUAUUUACACUCUAUCCUCCUGAAGGUGCACAUGUGCCUGACAGUACACUACUCAAGUCGACUUGGUUGAGACCCAUAGUAAAUGGGGAAGAAGGUUAUAGAUAUAUAGUAAAUGGACAUCCAGCACUCAAACGAGCUAACAUCCGGGUUGUUGGAAAGUUGGUGGCCCGAUCCAUAAGAGAAAGGAAAAUGAGACAACAUUAUAAGUCAUGUAAAGUUGAAUGAUGUUUCCAACAUAUUAUUACCUGUAAUAGUUAAACUUCUCUACCCAAAGAGACAAGUUAACACUGGAGGUGGAUCAAUUCUGUAUGAGUAGGAAGAAAGGAUAAAAAUCUUUGAAUAUAGAAAGAACUUUGACAAGUUUAUCUAUAAUUUCUAGUAUUUUUGGAUGAACACCAUUCAUUUGAUCUCCUUCAUAAAAAACAUCUCUUUUAUCAUAAUGAAGUAAACCUGCAGAGUGUCAAGUA